AGUGUUCCCGGAGCCGCGCCGAGUGAGGGGCCGCAGACUUUGCUCAUGGCGCAGCGGGUGCGUGGUGGGGGUGUUGUCCCUCCGCUAGGGUCAGGGCGAGGAUGGGGGCUCCUGCCCUGGCCGAAGACCUUCCUGUCCACCCAGCCCAGGCCAGCUUCAAUUUCCAACAGUGAGGGCAAGGCUUCCCCUCCUGCCUGGGCAGAGCGAGGUUUCCGCAGGCUCCACAAGGGGGAAGCCGGGAGGAAACUUGGGCCGGUGAGAAGUUUCCUUCUUUUUUUUUUUUUUUUUUUUUUUUGAGACGGAGUUUCGCACUUGUUGCCCAGACUGGAGUGCAAUGGCGCAAUCUCGGCUCACUGCAACCUCUGCCUCCCGGGUUCAAGCUAUUCUCCUGUCUCAAGCCUCCCUAGUAGCUGGGAUUACAGGUGCCCGCCACCAGGCGCGUCUAAUUUUUGCAUCUUUUAGUGGAGACGAGGUUUCACCAUGUUGGCCAGGCUGAUUCUGAACUCCUGACCUCAGGUGAUCCACCCGCCGCGGCCUCCCAAAGUGCUGCGAUUACAGGCAUGAGCCACCACCCCCGGCCUGUUUCCUUCUUUUUCUGCCUCCCAAACUGGGUUUGGAGGUUUUGCUGUUCUGUGUUGGGAGGAAAAGAGGCCGGAUCUGGAGCCGUUGGGCAGUGGCAGGUGUUGGGGGUGGCAUCCUGUCUCAGUCUCUGGAGUGACAGGGCCCGGGUUGGGGUCUCAACCGGGACUUCUGGUUGCAGGAGCUCAUGGCAAGGAUUUCUGCCACCCUCAAUAUCCGCCCCACCAACGUUUGGUCCUCCCCCUUCCUGGGGGACUGUGGUUGGAGAGAAGGGGAGAGACAGCUGGAAUCACUAUAGGCCUUUCUCCUCGGCUGCCCAUGGGGGGGUGGGGGAUUAGGCGGGUGCUUUGCUGCUGCAGUCCCCAAGCUGGCCUGGAAGCCUGGAGCUGCCUUGUCCUUGUCCCCUGUGUCCACCUCUCCCCAGCCUGUGUGAUUAAACCCCACCCCCACACCCCAUGGGAUGCAGGGGGAAAGGCUUGUGUAUUGCACUGGGGUGGGGGUACAUUUUUGCUUCGACUCUGAGUCCCCGUGAAAGAGUCCCUAGAGAAGUGUGCCUAGGUGGGGGUGGGCAUGAUGGCCUAGCUGGCAGCUGCUGGUUUCAGUUCCUGGGAAUCAGGCUGUAUGUGGUGGGUCUGCCUGGGGGUGGCUUAGGGGGCAGGCAGGAGGACACAGGUGCCUUUUUCACCUACCCCCAGGCUGCUUCAGACUUCUUUCUUGCCCCCUCACCCCUAGGCUAUACUUGGUUGCCCACGUGGCUCCUGUUAGGUCAUCAACAGCCACUGAAUCUGCCCUCAUUUUUACAAAUGGGGAAACUGAGGGAGGCCCGAGCCCUUGCCAACCAGGGCCUUCUGGACAGAGGACCAGACCUGAGCAUCCCGCUUCUUGGCUGCCAGAGCCAAGGCCCUGCCUGCUUUGUGGUUGGUGUCAUGGUAGAUUUUCCUGGGAAGCAGGCAUAGCUGGGCAGGGGCCUGGGCGGGUGGCAGGGGGUGCUGAGCUGGGGUGCUGCUGAUGGGAAGAGGGCUGGAGAGUGCCAGGAAGUCCUUGGUUUCUGGUUCUACCGGGGCCAAGUCUGCCCUCUGUCCCCUUUCCCUUUUCUUUCAUGUUUUCCCCAGAGUCCCCACCUCCCUGCUUCCUUUAGGGAUUAGCUAGUCUUGGUUAGAGAGGAAUGGGGGAAGCGGGGAGGGAACCACAGCCUCGGAGGCUGCGGAGAAGGACCGGAGACCGGGAGUGGGUGGCAGUCCUGCAUUUGUGGAAGAAGCUGUGGAGCAAUGUGGACCCACAAAGAUGGCACUUACGGUGGAACUCAUGGCAAAGAAGGAGUGGUACUGCUGGACUUUGCUGCAGCUGGAGGGGAGCUCGGCUGGCUCACACACCCGUAUGGCAAAGGGUGGGACCUGAUGCAGAACAUCAUGAAUGACAUGCCGAUCUACAUGUACUCCGUGUGCAACGUGAUGUCUGGCGACCAGGACAACUGGCUCCGCACCAACUGGGUGUACCGAGGAGAGGCUGAGCGUAUCUUCAUUGAGCUCAAGUUUACUGUACGUGACUGCAACAGCUUCCCUGGUGGCGCCAGCUCCUGCAAGGAGACUUUCAACCUCUACUAUGCCGAGUCGGACCUGGACUACGGCACCAACUUCCAGAAGCGCCUGUUCACCAAGAUUGACACCAUUGCGCCCGAUGAGAUCACCGUCAGCAGCGACUUCGAGGCACGCCACGUGAAGCUGAACGUGGAGGAGCGCUCCGUGGGGCCGCUCACCCGCAAAGGCUUCUACCUGGCCUUCCAGGAUAUCGGUGCCUGUGUGGCGCUGCUCUCCGUCCGUGUCUACUACAAGAAGUGCCCCGAGCUGCUGCAGGGCCUGGCCCACUUCCCUGAGACCAUCGCCGGCUCUGAUGCACCUUCCCUGGCCACUGUGGCCGGCACCUGUGUGGACCAUGCCGUGGUGCCACCGGGGGGUGAAGAGCCCCGUAUGCACUGUGCAGUGGAUGGCGAGUGGCUGGUGCCCAUUGGGCAGUGCCUGUGCCAGGCAGGCUACGAGAAGGUGGAGGAUGCCUGCCAGGCCUGCUCGCCUGGAUUUUUUAAGUUUGAGGCAUCUGAGAGCCCCUGCUUGGAGUGCCCUGAGCACACGCUGCCAUCCCCUGAGGGUGCCACCUCCUGCGAGUGUGAGGAAGGCUUCUUCCGGGCACCUCAGGACCCAGCGUCGAUGCCUUGCACACGACCCCCCUCCGCCCCACACUACCUCACAGCCGUGGGCAUGGGUGCCAAGGUGGAGCUGCGCUGGACGCCCCCUCAGGACAGCGGGGGCCGCGAGGACAUUGUCUACAGCGUCACCUGCGAACAGUGCUGGCCCGAGUCUGGGGAAUGCGGGCCGUGUGAGGCCAGUGUGCGCUACUCGGAGCCUCCUCACGGACUGACCCGCACCAGUGUGACAGUGAGCGACCUGGAGCCCCACAUGAACUACACCUUCACCGUGGAGGCCCGCAAUGGCGUCUCAGGCCUGGUAACCAGCCGCAGCUUCCGUACUGCCAGUGUCAGCAUCAACCAGACAGAGCCCCCCAAGGUGAGGCUGGAGGGCCGCAGCACCACCUCGCUUAGCGUCUCCUGGAGCAUCCCCCCGCCGCAGCAGAGCCGAGUGUGGAAGUACGAGGUCACUUACCGCAAGAAGGGAGACUCCAACAGCUACAAUGUGCGCCGCACCGAGGGUUUCUCCGUGACCCUGGACGACCUGGCCCCAGACACCACCUACCUGGUCCAGGUGCAGGCACUGACGCAGGAGGGCCAGGGGGCCGGCAGCAAGGUGCACGAAUUCCAGACGCUGUCCCCGGAGGGAUCUGGCAACUUGGCGGUGAUUGGCGGCGUGGCUGUCGGUGUGGUCCUGCUUCUGGUGCUGGCAGGAGUUGGCUUCUUUAUCCACCGCAGGAGGAAGAACCAGCGUGCCCGCCAGUCCCCGGAGGACGUUUACUUCUCCAAGUCAGAACAACUGAAGCCCCUGAAGACAUACGUGGACCCCCACACAUAUGAGGACCCCAACCAGGCUGUGUUGAAGUUCACUACCGAGAUCCAUCCAUCCUGUGUCACUCGGCAGAAGGUGAUCGGAGCAGGAGAGUUUGGGGAGGUGUACAAGGGCAUGCUGAAGACAUCCUCGGGGAAGAAGGAGGUGCCGGUGGCCAUCAAGACGCUGAAAGCCGGCUACACAGAGAAGCAGCGAGUGGACUUCCUCGGCGAGGCCGGCAUCAUGGGCCAGUUCAGCCACCACAACAUCAUCCGCCUAGAGGGCGUCAUCUCCAAAUACAAGCCCAUGAUGAUCAUCACUGAGUACAUGGAGAAUGGGGCCCUGGACAAGUUCCUUCGGGAGAAGGAUGGCGAGUUCAGCGUGCUGCAGCUGGUGGGCAUGCUGCGGGGCAUCGCAGCUGGCAUGAAGUACCUGGCCAACAUGAACUAUGUGCACCGUGACCUGGCUGCCCGCAACAUCCUCGUCAACAGCAACCUGGUCUGCAAGGUGUCUGACUUUGGCCUGUCCCGCGUGCUGGAGGACGACCCCGAGGCCACCUACACCACCAGUGGCGGCAAGAUCCCCAUCCGCUGGACCGCCCCGGAGGCCAUUUCCUACCGGAAGUUCACCUCUGCCAGCGACGUGUGGAGCUUUGGCAUUGUCAUGUGGGAGGUGAUGACCUAUGGCGAGCGGCCCUACUGGGAGUUGUCCAACCACGAGGUGAUGAAAGCCAUCAAUGAUGGCUUCCGGCUCCCCACACCCAUGGACUGCCCCUCCGCCAUCUACCAGCUCAUGAUGCAGUGCUGGCAGCAGGAGCGUGCCCGCCGCCCCAAGUUCGCUGACAUCGUCAGCAUCCUGGACAAGCUCAUUCGUGCCCCUGACUCCCUCAAGACCCUGGCUGACUUUGACCCCCGCGUGUCUAUCCGGCUCCCCAGCACGAGCGGCUCGGAGGGGGUGCCCUUCCGCACGGUGUCCGAGUGGCUGGAGUCCAUCAAGAUGCAGCAGUAUACGGAGCACUUCAUGGCGGCCGGCUACACUGCCAUCGAGAAGGUGGUGCAGAUGACCAACGACGACAUCAAGAGGAUUGGGGUGCGGCUGCCCGGCCACCAGAAGCGCAUCGCCUACAGCCUGCUGGGACUCAAGGACCAGGUGAACACUGUGGGGAUCCCCAUCUGAGCCUCGACAGGGCCUGGAGCCCCAUCGGCCAAGAAUACUUGAAGAAACAGAGUGGCCUCCCUGCUGUGCCAUGCUGGGCCACUGGGGACUUUAUUUAUUUCUAGUUCUUUCCUCCCCCUGCAACUUCCGCUGAGGGGUCUCGGAUGACACCCUGGCCUGAACUGAGGAGAUGACCAGGGAUGCUGGGCUGGGCCCUCUUUCCCUGCGAGACGCACACAGCUGAGCACUUAGCAGGCACCGCCACGUCCCAGCAUCCCUGGAGCAGGAGCCCCGCCACAGCCUUCGGACAGACAUAUGGGAUAUUCCCAAGCCGACCUUCCCUCCGCCUUCUCCCACAUGAGGCCAUCUCAGGAGAUGGAGGGCUUGGCCCAGCGCCAAGUAAACAGGGUACCUCAAGCCCCAUUUCCUCACACUAAGAGGGCAGACUGUGAACUUGACUGGGUGAGACCCAAAGCGGUCCCUGUCCCUCUAGUGCCUUCUUUAGACCCUCGGGCCCCAUCCUCAUCCCUGACUGGCCAAACCCUUGCUUUCCUGGGCCUUUGCAAGAUGCUUGGUUGUGUUGAGGUUUUUAAAUAUAUAUUUUGUACUUUGUGGAGAGAAUGUGUGUGUGUGGCAGGGGGCCCCGCCAGGGCUGGGGACAGAGGGUGUCAAACAUUCGUGAGCUGGGGACUCAGGGACCGGUGCUGCAGGAGUGUCCUGCCCAUGCCCCAGUCGGCCCCAUCUCUCAUCCUUUUGGAUAAGUUUCUAUUCUGUCAGUGUUAAAGAUUUUGUUUUGUUGGACAUUUUUUUCGAAUCUUAAUUUAUUAUUUUUUUUAUAUUUAUUGUUAGAAAAUGACUUAUUUCUGCUCUGGAAUAAAGUUGCAGAUGAUUCAAACCGA